AGAGGCGGGUCGCAGCGGCGCAGAGGAGGUCAGCUGCGGGAGCGUUUCCGGGGACGGUGCCGCCAUGAGAUUGACCCCGCGCGCGCUGUGCAGCGCCGCCCAGGCCGCCUGGCGGGAGAACUUCCCCCUGUGCGGUCGCGACGUGGCGCGCUGGUUCCCGGGCCACAUGGCCAAGGGGCUGAAGAAGAUGCAGAGCAGCCUGAAGCUGGUGGACUGUAUCAUCGAGGUCCACGAUGCCCGGAUCCCACUUUCAGGCCGCAACCCUCUGUUUCAGGAAACCCUUGGGCUUAAGCCUCACUUGCUGGUCCUCAACAAGAUGGACUUGGCGGAUCUUACAGAGCAGCAGAAAAUUAUGCAACACUUAGAAGGAGAAGGCCUAAAAAAUGUCAUUUUUACCAACUGUGUAAAGGAUGAAAAUGUCAAGCAGAUCAUCCCGAUGGUCACUGAACUGAUUGGGAGAAGCCACCGCUACCACCGAAAAGAGAACCUGGAGUACUGUAUCAUGGUCAUUGGGGUCCCCAACGUGGGCAAGUCCUCCCUCAUCAACUCCCUCCGGAGGCAGCACCUCAGGAAAGGGAAAGCCACCAGGGUGGGUGGCGAGCCUGGGAUCACCAGAGCUGUGAUGUCCAAAAUUCAGGUCUCUGAGCGGCCCCUGAUGUUCCUGUUGGACACUCCUGGCGUGCUGGCUCCUCGGAUUGAAAGUGUGGAGACAGGCCUGAAGCUGGCCCUGUGUGGAACGGUGCUGGACCACCUGGUCGGGGAGGAGACCAUGGCUGACUACCUGCUGUACACCCUCAACAAACACCAGCGCUUUGGGUACGUGCAGCACUACGGCCUGGGCAGUGCCUGUGACAACGUAGAGCGCGUGCUGAAGAGUGUGGCUGUGAAGCUGGGGAAGACGCAGAAGGUGAAGGUGCUCACGGGCACGGGUAACGUGAACAUUAUUCAGCCUAACUAUCCUGCGGCAGCCCGUGACUUCCUGCAGACUUUCCGCCGUGGGCUGCUGGGUUCCGUGAUGCUGGACCUCGACGUCCUGCGGGGCCACCCCCCGGCUGAGACUUUGCCCUGAACUUGUCCGGGUAGGGAGGGCCGGAGGCAUGUGGCCUCCCAGACCUCCUGACCUGGGUGGUUGAGGCUCAAGACAGCUCACCCGGUCCAGAAGCUCCAUGCUGGUCACUAGGGUGCUGUGCUCUCUGGCGCCCCACAGCCUGGCCAGCUCCAGGGACCCCAGUUGCAGGGCCCAAGCAGGUGGGAGUGGACACCAGGCUUCCCAGUGGACGUCCCUGAGCAGCUCCGCAUGCUUGGUUCUCCCGGAGCUUCCUGCUCAGGCCUCUUGAGAAAUGGAUGCUGUCUCAGAAGGAGUUAAAGCUAUAACCUGUAACCUUUAAAAUCUCCAGUUAAAGGGCCUGUUUCUUACUGGCCUGUGAGGUGCACCGUAGUGCCUUGGGCCUGUGUGUUAAAGCUGCUCUCACCAGUGAAACCUAAGAAAUGAGCAGGUUGGCAGCUAGGGUUUGUGUUGGAGGCUUUCGGUCCAGUGUCUUGCAGUCCUACAACAAGUGAGAGGCUUGCUGCCAUCAGAGAGGUUUAUUUCACACUUACAGGCACACACAGACACAGACCAGAGACUCCCAGCAGCAGAGCCCAAGCACUGGCUUCGCCCCUCAGUGCCCUGGGGCAUGUUCAGGGCAGGGUUGAGGGGGACGCCCUGCACAUGGCUUUGCUGUGCAAUGACUGGAAGGCCGCCCGGCAUGGGCAGUAGAGACCCCUGGCCUCUGAGCACCUUCUAGCUCACGGGUAGUGGGAUUCUGCAUUAGUGGGGCUGAGAGAUGUGGGGGCCCCUCCAGCCCCAUUAUAGUGCACCUGAAGGGGUCCACAGCCUGUGUCCUAGAAGAGGGAAGAGGAAGGAAGGUGGGUGGGGCUGGUAGUAUGGACUAAGGUGCUGCAGGACCUGGGGCCAGGGACAUCCUGUGCAGAAGCUCCGGCUGCCUCUUUGCGGUGGUGGCCUGACCGUCCCACAGCAGCCUCCACCAGGGCCCUGGUGCUCAGUGGCCCCUCUUUGCUGGCUGGCUGCCUCUGCUGCCCCAUACCCCACACACUCAUCAGCCUGAAGUUAGCCCCUGAGUGCCACCUGCAUCGUGCCAUAACCCUGACCGCCUGGGGCAGGAAGUAUUCAGGUUGGCUGUGUCAGAUGCUAAUGUGCUGAAUCAACAGUCAUUGCAGAUCACGAAGUGUCCAUCAUAACUGGAACAUUCCAUCAGCUUGCAGUGCUGUGGUGUGUGAGGGUCUGGUGCAGCUCAGCCCAUUUUCCAGGUGGGCAUCUGCAAAGUUGAGGGGGCUCCGGUGGGUCUCUCUGCUGUGAGGAGACUCAGACCACCCCCUGCCUCCUGGGGGAAAUGUCAGAAGGGCUUCUCUGCCUAUGAGGAUCUGGGGCAGGGCUUGGCCUUGGCCUGCUGGUCUUGGAGGCGUUGAGCUUGGUCUGGAAGGGGUGGAGGAGCGUCUGGGCUCACUGGGCCAGGGGCAUUGCUGGCAGUGUGGACGGGAGGCUGCAGGGCGCUGCCUCCUGUGGCUUAGUGCCCUGGAGCUAGAGAGCAGUGCUUGGUUGAGUCCUGCCAACAGCUUCCAGAUCCUCACCCAGGCCAGAACCCAGGCCAGCUGGGGAAGGCAGAGGCUGGCAGGGCCCGUGGUGGGUGCUGGUCUUGACUUUGGUGUCCACUGAGUCCCGAGGCUCAGGCCCAGGAGGGAUGCAGUCCGGCUGAGGGCGAGGCUGUCCCCAGGACAUGGAGAGGGUGAGAUCCCAAGGCCACGGCGGGGGGCAGGGAGAACCCCUCCUACCCUGGAUGAGUGGGUGACUGGAGAGCUAGAGAACGUGGCAGACCCAAGACCUCUCAGUGCUGAGCCCAUGGAGGAUGCCCCAGGCUGGCGGGACUGGGAAGCAGAGGGCUGGUCUUAACACAGGUGUGUCCAGUGCUGGAGGCAAGUCCUUGUCGUGACUGUCCAGCGCCACUCCAUGUCUCUCCUGUCCUUGGAUGUUGGGGGGCUCAGCCUCUUGCAUGGGUGUCCUGCUGGGCGCUGGGCCCCGCCACUGGCCCCCUGCUUGCUUUGGGGUCUGAGUUAGCUCCUGGCUCCACUGAGCAGGCCGUCAGCUGCCAGCCCACCACGCGGAUACCCAGGCCCUGUUCCGAGGCCUGGAACAGCUGCUUCCGAAGAAGGGGCUGCCUUCAGGGAAAUGCGUGCACCGUGCAGCCUGUGCUGUGCCCAGGGAGGCCUCUUCAGCGGGAUUGGCAGUUGCUGUGCCCUGAGAACAGGCAGAACUGUGUGAUCCCUGAAUGUGAACCUGAAGUUCAAAGGACUUGGAAAGCUCUGGAAUGUGUUGGUUUUUCCCCCCCAAAAUGGGUCCUAAGGAGGGUAAAGUGACUUGUUUCAA